AAGGUGUCCAGCGCCGCGACCGGCUGGUCGUCCGCCUCGGCCCCCGCCCGCGUCCCCUUUCCCCCGGGGCGCAGCGCUACGGCGGGCGCGGGCCGCCCGGCGCAUUGUUCGCAGCCUUCGCGGCGGUGCGCUGCUGACUUUAUUUGUGCGCUUUGCGUGUGCGUGAGGUUGCACCUUUUGUAGGCUGGCGAGUCUCUGGACGAGGAUGGGACGGGGGACACGGGCCCAGUUGCGGCCCUGCGCGAGCGGGACCUGUCAGCCCUGAGGUGCAGCGGACCCUCCGGCAUGGCCGGAAAAUCGAGGCCGGGGAGAAGGCAGCGUGGCCGGGAAGCUGCCGCCUUAAACCCGGACCAGUGCAGGAUUGCUUCCUGCGUAGCCGUCCCGGUUAUUGUAACACGCUUUGCAAGCUAACGACUGGGGUUUGUGAGGGGGUUUGUUUAUUUUUCUAAGUGUUUGCAAAGAUGCCGAGGUCGAGGCGGGCUGCGAGGAGACGGUCCGCGCCUACCCCCACCGCACCCUGGCCUCGGUGGGGCUGGGAGAGGGCUGGGGCUCCGGAGAAGGGGCUGGAGGUUCGCGAAGCGCGCGUCUCCAUCCCUCCGCCCCGAUGGGGGCGGGGAAGGGGUGCAGUAGACCGCGCUGGAAGAGCAGCUCUCUGGGGAGGGGUCUCCCUUGCCGCGGCAGGCGCAGCAGGCCGGGGAGGGGGGUUGCCUAGGAGAGGGGCCGGGCGGCGGAGGGGAGGGGAGGAGAGGGGGCGCGGGUGCAGCCGCCGCGCGCGCUCGCCCCUCCUCGCGCGCCAUGACUGUGGAACGUGGUGCCGGGGAGGAGGGACGGCCACCGGGGGCCGCCCGGGGCUGCUCGGCAUUGGUGCGGAAACCCGAGCCCGGAGUCGCUCCCUCGCGCUGUCUCCUCCUCCUCCUCUGCGGGGGAAACCGCUGCACCCAAACCGGGAGCAGCUGCGAGCAGGGGGCAGGGCGCGGGCUGAAAGGCGAGCCGAAGGUUCAAACCUCCGCGGCGCGGGCGGGGGCGGAGGGCAACAGCAGGACGGCCCCCAGGUCCCGAGAAGGCGUGGCAGUGGUCGGCCCAGGUGUCAGGGAACCUGGCCUGAGACCCCUGCAUUUCCAAGCUUCUUUCCUGGUCAGAGGAAACGUGAACCAAAGGUAGUUCAGCUAAACAGACCACCUCGAGCCGGGUUCGAGGCAUCUGUCUCGAGGGCAAGACAGUAUUUUUUGCACGACAGAAAGUUACACCAUCCAUUUUUUUCCGUGGGGGAAAUCAUUGCGCCCCUUCCCCCAAAAUGUCGCGCAAGAAGAAUGACCUCCCGCUACCCAGACCUUCGCCAGUGUCCCCCACCCCACCCCCACCCGGGCGCUGGGUGUGGAUUGGGCGGAGGGAGGCUAUAUGGGAGCUUAAAGCAUGAGGUCAUGAGCGGAGGAGACUGCUGCCAAAAGCACCCGAGGUUUUUGUGUUUUUUGAGGGGUAACGGUUCUCCAUCUUCAGCAGUGGAAAGUCCUCCCGCCUACCCUACCAAUUCUGGGGCACGUGGACCACAGAGUCCCUGAAAAGAGGAGGGGACCCGGGCUAUUUCGCUUAAUGAGCGUUUGGCGCGUGCCCAGCCCUUUAUGGAGCCCUUCCACAUAAGCAAAGAAAGCCGAGGGACAGCGCACAGUGUUGCGGCGACUGGGAAAGGCUUCAGAUGCUCGAUGUCCCCCGCCCUCUUUCCUCAGUCCUCGGUCAUCUUCCAAGUGGGCUGCUUUCUGCGAUAGCUUCCUGUCCCCCUCCGACCCAUUCCUCCCAAGCGACUAAAACUCCUAAUGACAUUAUUUUAAAGCCUUCAAAACCCUCUUCCAUUGCCCUUAGAAUAAAGCCAAGUUGUGAUUUCGCCUCUACAGACCUCUCUACCCGCCCAGCUCUUCCUCGGAUAUUGUAAGCCCCGUCAAGCUUUCUUUGUUCAAGGGGUGGAGGAGGGGGCGCCUAACCUUUCCCCUUCCACCUCUUCUUACUAACUCCUGCUGGACCUUCAAGAUUUGACUCAACUGUCAGUAACUUCAAGAUGCCUUCCUGAGGGUACACCCAGGUCUCUACCUCAGGGGAAAAGACCUACCCUAGGUCUCCUGGCAGCAGCGCUGUGGCCGGAGUUGGCCCCAGUGGCGGCCUUUUUCCAAGCGGAGGAGGAACAGCCAAGCUAAGCUUGACCACCGUCACCGCCCAGGGACCUGAGCGGGAGCUGGCUAGGACAAAACCUCAAAACGGGACUUGGGAAAACCGCACCACCCAGAAAACUCAGCCCCUCCACCUCCCUCCCAGCACACACACACACCCUCUUAAUCUAAAACUCCUCCCCGGGGCAGAUAAGGAACCUAUUCGGAGAGUUAAGUUAAUUGCCCCAGGUCAAUGUGGAAAUUCACAGCCUGUCUUUCCAGCUCCUAAACCAGAAGCUGCAGAGAAGGAAGGAUUUGGGAUUUGCGGCUACACAGCCAAGGACGCUUUUGUCAUCUUCAAAGGACCCCCUACACCCUACACGCUUGGCCCGCUCUGUUCAUUGCCAACAGAGUGAUGGUAAUGCCAGAUGGUUAGCUCUGCAGGCUCUGACCUUAGGCAAAUUACUUAACCGCUUGGUUCAGUUUCUUUGCCUGUAAAAUGGGAAUGAUAGUAUUCAUAUCAUAGUGUUAUUGUGAGGUUUAAAUGAGUUAUUUUAUGUAAGGCCUUAGAGUUUAAAGCAAGUUACUAAUAUUUGUGAAUAGGGUUGUGUAUCCUCCCCCGCCCCGCCCCCCCCCCACCUUCCAAAGGACUCUAGAAAAUCAGAUCCUCAGAGUCUUAGCUGAUUGAAGCAUCAGAAAAAUAUCUAUGGGGCCAGGCGGGGUGGCUCACACCUGUCAUCCCAGCGCUUUGGGCGGAUGAGGUAGGCGGAUCGCUUGAGCUGAGGAGUUUGAGACCAGCCUGGACAAUGUAGAGAGACCCUCUCCACGUUUAUUAUUAAAAAAUAAAAAAUUAGCCAGGCAUAGUGGUGCAUGCCUGUAGUCCCAGCUACUGAGGAGGCUAAGGCAGGAGGAUGGCUUGAGCCCACGGGGUUGAGGCUGCAGUGAGCAGAUUGCCCCACUGCACUCCAGCCUGGGUGACAGCGCAAGACUCUGUCUCAAAAAAUAAAAUUAUAUAUAUAGAGAGAGGGAGAGAGAGAGAGAGAAAGAGAGCACCAAAAGGACUGGGAAACACCGGCAGAUGCACAGACAAUGCAUCCCUGAUUUUACCAAUAGACUUGACUCCCAACAAUGCAUACUCUUGAAGGCAAUCCACAGGUUGAAUAAACCAAGUCCAUGAGCGCUGGGUCUGGAAUCUUUCUACAAUCAGGGUCAGAAGGAGGGUGACUGAAAUUAAAAUAUUAGCUUGGAUCUUUGAAAUCAGAGUCAGGCUGAAAAAGUCCCAAUCUUAGUUCAAAACCUGUCCUGCAUGACUGAAGCCCUCCUAGGGCUGCACAAAGUAUAAUGGAAUUAUUAUUAUUAUUAUCAUUAGAUCCUAGUCUUACCAUUCUCAGCACUUAUCCCCAUAGCAAAAGACCAUUUUUUAAUGUAAUUUAUUCUUUUGGAAUAGGUUGAAUGCAUUCACAUGGUUCCAAAUUCAAAUAAACAGCAAGAAGUCUCCCUCCCACCCUGUCUGCCACCCACUUGGUUUUCCUUCUCUGGAGGCAACCUGGGUUAGUGGUCAGAAGAUGCAUUUAACUGUUUUCCAGCUGAGGCCUUGUGAGAACUCCUCGGACACCAAUUUAAAUCUUUAUGUCCAGAACUCCUUUCUCCAAUCCAGAGAUGAGGUUCCACCAUUCUUGCCCAGACUGGUUUCGAACUCCUGGACUCAAGCGAUUUGCCUGCCUCGGCCUCAAAAAGUGCUGGGAUUACAUGCAUGAGCCACCACACCCGGACCCUCUCUCUUAAAUAGUGGCCCUUUUGCCUCUCUGCAACACAGGAAAAAUUCUGUUAGCCUGCAUCAGAAGGAGUGGCAUGGAGGCUUUGGAGUUAAGAAGAUUUAAUUCAAAUUAUGUGUCCGGUGCCUGCCAGCAAUGAGACCUUGGUAAGGUUUCUUAACCUCUCUGAGCUGGGACCAUACCUUCUGCGUUGGUUUAAUAUAAAGGUUAAAUGCAUGUAAAUAAAUGACUUCUAAAAUAAAUAACAUUCUAAAAUGUUAGUAACAACUAAAUACAAUAUUUAGAUCUUGUGAGGAUUUGAUUUGAAUAAAUAAGAUUUUUUUAAAAGACA